AUCCAGAUUUGCUUUUACAUUUUCUUGCCUGAGUCUGAGGUGAACAGUGAACAUAUUUACAUUUGAUUUAACAGUGAACCUUAAUUCUUUCUGGCUUCACAGUGAAACAAGUUUAUGCAAUCGAUCAAAUAUUUUCAUCCCUGAGGUUAACAAUUACCAUCAAAAUGUUUUGUGGAGACUAUGUGCAAGGAACCAUCUUCCCAGCUCCCAAUUUCAAUCCCAUAAUGGAUGCCCAAAUGCUAGGAGGAGCACUCCAAGGAUUUGACUGUGACAAAGACAUGCUGAUCAACAUUCUGACUCAGCGCUGCAAUGCACAAAGGAUGAUGAUUGCAGAGGCAUACCAGAGCAUGUAUGGCCGGGCCCAGUGUGUGUUGUUCUCCUCCAUGUGUCCAUGUGUUCUCAUCAUUCAGCUCCUACUUGACCUGAUUGGGGAUAUGAGGGAGCAGCUUUCGGAUCACUUCAAAGAUGUGAUGGCUGGCCUCAUGUACCCACCACCACUGUAUGAUGCUCAUGAGCUCUGGCAUGCCAUGAAGGGAGUAGGCACUGAUGAGAAUUGCCUCAUUGAAAUACUAGCUUCAAGAACAAAUGGAGAAAUUUUCCAGAUGCGAGAAGCCUACUGCUUGCAAUACAGCAAUAACCUCCAAGAGGACAUUUAUUCAGAGACCUCAGGACACUUCAGAGAUACUCUCAUGAACUUGGUCCAGGGGACCAGAGAGGAAGGAUAUACAGACCCUGCGAUGGCUGCUCAGGAUGCAAUGGUCCUAUGGGAAGCCUGUCAGCAGAAGACGGGGGAGCACAAAACCAUGCUGCAAAUGAUCCUGUGCAACAAGAGCUACCAGCAGCUGCGGCUGGUUUUCCAGGAAUUUCAAAAUAUUUCUGGGCAAGAUAUGGUAGAUGCCAUUAAUGAAUGUUAUGAUGGAUACUUUCAGGAGCUGCUGGUUGCAAUUGUUCUCUGUGUUCGAGACAAACCAGCCUAUUUUGCUUAUAGAUUAUAUAGUGCAAUUCAUGACUUUGGUUUCCAUAAUAAAACUGUAAUCAGGAUUCUCAUUGCCAGAAGUGAAAUAGACCUGCUGACCAUAAGGAAACGAUACAAAGAGCGAUAUGGAAAAUCCCUAUUUCAUGAUAUCAGAAAUUUUGCUUCAGGGCAUUAUAAGAAAGCACUGCUUGCCAUCUGUGCUGGUGAUGCUGAGGACUACUAAAAUGAAGAGGACUUGGAGUACUGUGCACUCCUCUUUCUAGACACUUCCAAAUAGAGAUUUUCUCACAAAUUUGUACUGUUCAUGGCACUAUUAACAAAACUAUACAAUCAUAUUUUCUCUUCUAUCUUUGAAAUUAUUCUAAGCCAAAGAAAACUAUGAAUGAAAGUAUAUGAUACUGAAUUUGCCUACUAUCCUGAAUUUGCCUACUAUCUAAUCAGCAAUUAAAUAAAUUGUGCAUGAUGGAAUAAUAGAAAAAUUGCAUUGGAAUAGAUUUUAUUUAAAUGUGAACCAUCAACAACCUA